AUUCAAGCCUGGGCCCUGGAAGGAGGGGUGGACAGUCCCCUCCCUUCCAGUCCAGCAUGGGUCUGGGGAAGAGAAGCAGCUUUGCCUGGAAGGGGCCUCCUAGGAGGGGGAGCGGUGGUUUCUAGCUCAGGCUUUAGGAUCAGAGAGCAGCAGAUUCAAAUCCUGACGGUUUUGGUAAAGUCAAUUCAAUCUCUCCAAGACUCCGUUUAUUUGAUCUGCGAAGUGGGGAUAAUGGUAUCACGUCGCAGGGUUGUCAGGCGGAGCUGGUAGGGGAGCUGCCCCCCAGAGCAGCAUGGAUGCCCCGCGAAGGGACAUGGAGUUGCUCAGCAACAGCCUGGCUGCCUACGCGCACAUCCGCGCCAACCCCGAGAGCUUCGGCCUCUACUUCGUGCUGGGCGUCUGCUUCGGCCUGCUGCUCACCCUCUGCCUGCUCGUCAUCAGCAUCUCGUGGGCGCCCCGCCCGCGGCCCCGGGGCCCGGCUCAGCGCCGGGACCCCCGCAGCAGCACCCUGGAGCCCGAGGACGACGACGAGGACGAGGAGGACACGGUGACUCGGCUGGGCCCCGACGACACGCUGCCGGGCCCCGAGCUGUCCGCAGAGCCGGACGGGCCCCUCAACGUCAACGUCUUCACGUCGGCGGAGGAGCUGGAGCGGGCGCAGCGGCUGGAGGAGCGCGAACGGAUCCUGCGGGAGAUCUGGCGCACCGGGCAGCCGGACCUGCUGGGCACAGGCACGCUGGGGCCCAGCCCCACGGCCACGGGCACCCUGGGCCGCAUGCACUAUUACUGAUGGGCCCCGGCUCCCGCUGCAAGGCGCUCGGGGUACCGGACCUGCACAUGAGCUCAGAGCUACCCCACACCUUCGGACUGCCUCGGCCCCCACAGCUCCCAGGUGCUACUGGGCGUGGACCGCCACCCCCUGAGAGGCUCCCUUCCCCAGUCCUGCCAGAAGACCCCGGGGGCGGGGAGGGGGCAGCAUGCAGGGUCCCCACUCCCUCUCUGGGGUCGAUGAAGAGGUGAAGUGACCAAAUGAAAGAAAGCUGCAUUCUCAGUGA